AGACUCCUGGGUCCGGUCAACCGUCAAAAUGUCCAAAGAACCUCUCAUUCUCUGGCUGAUGAUUGAGUUUUGGUGGCUUUACCUGACACCAGUCACUUCAGAGACUGUUGUGACGGAGGUUUUGGGUCACCGGGUGACUUUGCCCUGUCUGUACUCAUCCUGGUCUCACAACAGCAACAGCAUGUGCUGGGGGAAAGACCAGUGCCCCUACUCCGGUUGCAAGGAGGCGCUCAUCCGCACUGAUGGAAUGAGGGUGACCUCAAGAAAGUCAGCAAAAUAUAGACUUCAGGGGACUAUCCCGAGAGGUGAUGUCUCCUUGACCAUCUUAAACCCCAGUGAAAGUGACAGCGGUGUGUACUGCUGCCGCAUAGAAGUGCCUGGCUGGUUCAACGAUGUAAAGAUAAACGUGCGCCUGAAUCUACAGAGAGCCUCAACAACCACGCACAGAACAGCAACCACCACCACACGCAGAACAACAACAACAAGCCCCACCACCACCCGACAAAUGACAACAACCCCAGCUGCACUUCCAACAACAGUCGUGACCACACCCGAUCUCACAACCGGAACACCACUCCAGAUGACAACCAUUGCCGUCUUCACAACAGCAAACACGUGCCUUUCACUAACCCCAAGCACCCUUCCGGAGGAAGCCACAGGUCUUCUGACUCCCGAGCCUUCUAAGGAAGGGCCCAUCCUCACUGCAGAAUCAGAAACUGUCCUCCCCAGUGAUUCCUGGAGUAGUGUUGAGUCUACUUCUGCUGACACUGUCCUGCUGACAUCCAAAGAGUCCAAAGUUUGGGAUCUCCCAUCAACAUCCCACGUGUCAAUGUGGAAAACGAGUGAUUCUGUGUCUUCUCCUCAGCCUGGAGAGAUGAGUUCUCACCAUGUUGCCCAGGCUGGUCUCAAAUCUCUUGGCCUCAAGUGAUCCUCCUGCCUUGGCCUCUCAAAGUUCUAGAGCCAGCUUGCCUGGCCUGGGGCUGUGUUCUCAUGAGUGGCUUGUCUUUGGAUGUGGAAACAAUCUGUCAUCUAUCUGGUUGUCUUGGGAUUCAACUAUUCUGGCUCCUUCGUGGCCACGUACCACAUCCUCCCGCCAGCUGGAGUGGAAGCAAAACAUGCUGCAAGCAUCAGUGCUGGCUUCUCCUCUCCUCUGCUCAUCUCUGAAGUCCCUCUGUUGAAAUCUUCCUUCUUCCUUAGCAACUGCUGACCUUAUGCCAGGAAUGAUAGUAGGAAAACCACCUAUUCAUAUUUCAAAUUUUGUUUUUUUAUUUUAAAUUACACAAAUGUCACACUAAUGCAUUUUUGUUAGGAGUGCAUAGAAACAGAUAGAAAUAAAAUUCUCUUUCACUCCUUGUCUUCAAUCCCAGCCCCCUGCCAUGAGAUAAUAACUGUUAUUAGUUGAAGAUGAUCAUUCUAGGUCUUUUUUCCAUUCCCUUAUGUGUCUACAUAGCUAUAGAAAUACAUAGUUCAGUUUUGUGCAUGUCUUUAGACAAUGUUAUCAUGCUAUAUGCAGCAUUCUGCAUUUUGUUUUAUUCACUUAUUGUUAUAUAUUGGACCACUUUCUUCUUUAAUCUAUGUAGAUACAUGUCAAAUUGCUGUGUAAUAUUUCACAUUAUGAGUACUCACAGUAUUUCUUGUCUAUUGAGGGGCAUUUAGGUUGUUUCAAUGUUUCCUUUUUAUAAACAGUGCUGCAGUGAACAUCCUAGCACAUGCAUACCUCCCUAACCAUUCAUGCAAGUGUUUCUGUAGUUAGGAUGGUGACCAAAAAGUAAAAAUUGCUGGUUAAAAGAAAUGUGCACCUUUAAAUUUAAUAGCUUGUAGAAAAAUGUUCUCAGAAAAGGCUGUGCCAAUUUAUUUUUCCACCCACAGAGUAUCUGCUUUCCCAUAUUCUCCCUACACUUGAUAUGACUGUUUGUUUAACUUUUUCAAUCUUAUGAGAAGAAAAUGUCAUCUUGUUCUUUUCUUUUUUCUUUCUUUCUAUUUUAUUUUUUUUUUGAGACAGAGCCUCACUCUG